GCAGACCAGAGGGUGACCCGGAUGAUGGCGGCCGGCGCGGCCCUAGCCCUGGCCUUGUGGCUACUAAUGCCACCAGUGGAGGUGGGAGGGGCGGGGCCCCCGCCAAUCCAGGACGGUGAGUUCACGUUCCUGUUGCCGGCGGGGAGGAAGCAGUGUUUCUACCAGUCCGCGCCGGCCAACGCAAGCCUCGAGACCGAAUACCAGGUGAUCGGAGGUGCUGGACUGGACGUGGACUUCACGCUGGAGAGCCCUCAGGGCGUGCUGUUGGUCAGCGAGUCCCGCAAGGCUGAUGGGGUACACACGGUGGAGCCAACGGAGGCCGGGGACUACAAGCUGUGCUUUGACAACUCCUUCAGCACCAUCUCCGAGAAGCUGGUGUUCUUUGAACUGAUCUUUGACAGCCUCCAGGAUGACGAGGAGGUCGAAGGAUGGGCAGAGGCUGUGGAGCCCGAGGAGAUGCUGGAUGUUAAAAUGGAGGACAUCAAGGAGUCCAUUGAGACCAUGCGGACCCGGCUGGAGCGCAGCAUCCAGAUGCUCACGCUACUGCGGGCCUUCGAGGCACGUGACCGCAACCUGCAAGAGGGCAACUUGGAGCGGGUCAACUUCUGGUCAGCUGUCAACGUGGCGGUGCUGCUGCUGGUGGCUGUGCUGCAGGUCUGCACGCUCAAGCGCUUCUUCCAGGACAAGCGCCCGGUGCCCACGUAGCCCCUGCCAUGGAAGGAAGAACGGGACAAAGGAGGGGCAGCAGGGUGUGUGCAUAUGAGACUUGGGGGUCCCUCCCCAAUUUUAGUUUCCUGCCAAAACGGGAGUGUGCAGUCAGGGCCUGCGGUCUGGCCCCAUGAGUCUCCUUCCGUCCUCAGCGGGCAGGGAACACCUCUGGCUUGUAGAAGGGACGGCUCAGUGGCUGCACCGACGGUCCUGGAAAUCUCACAUGGUGGGCACUGCAGCGUUGGAACGUGAGCCUCGGAUUUCCUGGCCCCUCUACUGUAAAUGUGCCUUAGCCUAAGCCUCCCAUCCUGUGUUAGCGUUGCCUGGUGCGGGGCAGGGCCUAACAAGGAAACCUGGGCCCUCCAAGCCAGGUUGAGGUCUGGUAACAGAAUGCCAGGAAGGGGGCCUGGAAGACCACCUGCCCCGGCCCCUCUCCUGCAGGGGCCCCACACAGGCAUGAGGGAUGGCCCGGCCAAAGUCUAGGCAGAAGCCUCCUAUAACAAAGGGUGGUGUGGCCUGGGCAUUGGAGUCAAUAAAUUAUGGUCAGAAAAUCACAAGAGCCUGCUGAUUGGGGCUCAGGGACACCAGCCAGGACAGACCGGCCCCCGAGGGGGCAGCCAGACAGGUGGGAGGGGCCUCCCACGAAGCUCAGAAGAAAGGUCGUGCGGGAGCCGAUGGAGGUGGUCGCCUGGCACAAGAGAAAAAUCAGAAAGCAAAGUUUAACUGAGCCCCAGUUGGGCCACGAGGCUUGGGCUUCCCCACGAGGUGAGAGAAGCAGGGCCUGAGGGUAGGAAGGGGGUGGAGCGCUGGGGUCCCCGCUUCACCAGGCAGCAGCCAGGCCUGUGCACGUGGGGGUGUGCAGGGGGUCAGAGAAUAUCUGCUCCCACUCCUCACAUGCUAAGGAAAGUAAAAGCUCUCCCCUGUA